GCAGCUGCGGGACUCAGAGGCGAAGCUUGAGGGGCUCAGGAAGGACGAAGAACCACCCUUGAGAGAAGAGGCAGCAGCAGCGGCGGCAGCAGCAGCGGCAGCGACCCCACCACUGCCACAUUUGCCAGGAAACAAUGCUGCUAGCGACAUUCAAGCUGUGCGCUGGGAGCUCCUACAGACACAUGCGCAACAUGAAGGGGCUGAGGCAACAGGCUGUGAUGGCCAUCAGCCAGGAGCUGAACCGGAGGGCCCUGGGGGGCCCCACCCCUAGCACGUGGAUUAACCAGGUUCGGCGGCGGAGCUCUCUACUCGGUUCUCGGCUGGAAGAGACUCUCUACAGUGACCAGGAGCUGGCCUAUCUCCAGCAGGGGGAGGAGGCCAUGCAGAAGGCCUUGGGCAUCCUUAGCAACCAAGAGGGCUGGAAGAAGGAGAGUCAGCAGGACAAUGGGGACAAAGUGAUGAGUAAAGUGGUCCCAGAUGUGGGCAAGGUGUUCCGGCUGGAGGUCGUGGUGGACCAGCCCAUGGAGAGGCUCUAUGAAGAGCUCGUGGAGCGCAUGGAAGCAAUGGGGGAGUGGAACCCCAAUGUCAAGGAGAUCAAGGUCCUGCAGAAGAUCGGAAAAGAUACAUUCAUUACUCACGAGCUGGCUGCCGAGGCAGCAGGAAACCUGGUGGGGCCCCGUGACUUUGUGAGCGUGCGCUGUGCCAAGCGCCGAGGCUCCACCUGUGUGCUGGCUGGCAUGGCCACAGACUUCGGGAACAUGCCUGAGCAGAAGGGUGUCAUCAGGGCGGAGCACGGUCCCACUUGCAUGGUGCUUCACCCGUUGGCUGGAAGUCCCUCUAAGACCAAACUUACGUGGCUACUCAGCAUCGACCUCAAGGGGUGGCUGCCCAAGAGCAUCAUCAACCAGGUCCUGUCCCAGACCCAGGUGGAUUUUGCCAACCACCUGCGCAAGCGCCUGGAGUCCCACCCUGCCUCUGAAGCCAGGUGUUGAAGACCAGCCUGCUGUUCCCAACUGUGCCCAGCUGCACUGGUACACACGCUCAUCAGGAGAAUCCCUACUGGAAGCCUGCAAGUCUAAGAUCUCCAUCUGGUGACAGUGGGAUGGGUGGGGUUCGUGUUUAGAGUAUGACACUAGGAUUCAGAUUGGUGAAAGUUUUUAGUACCAAGAAAACAGGGAUGAGGCUCUUGGAUUAAAAGGUAACUUCAUUCACUGAUUAGCUAUGACAUGAGGGUUCAGGCCCCUAAAAUAAUUGUAAAACUUUUUUUCUGGGCCCUUAUGUACCCACCUAAAACCAUCUUUAAAAUGCUAGUGGCUGAUAUGGGUGUGGGGGAUGCUAACCACAGGGCCUGAGAAGUCUUGCUUUAUGGGCUCAAGAAUGCCAUGCGCUGGCAGUACAUGUGCACAAAGCAGAAUCUCAGAGGGUCUCCUGCAGCCCUCUGCUCCUCCCGGCCGCUGCACAGCAACACCACAGAACAAGCAGCACCCCACAGUGGGUGCCUUCCAGAAAUAUAGUCCAAGCUUUCUCUGUGGAAAAAGACAAAACUCAUUAGUAGACAUGUUUCCCUAUUGCUUUCAUAGGCACCAGUCAGAAUAAAGAAUCAUAAUUCACACAAACAUCAGUCUUUGUUUUAAUAUUGUACUGUUAAAAAAAUCUAUGCAGCUGGGUGCAGUGGCUCACGCCUGUAAUCCCAGCAUUUUGGGAGGCUGAGGUAGGCGGAUCACAAGGUCAGGAGAUCGAGACCAUCCUGGCCAACAUGGUGAAACCCCGUCUCUACUAAAAUACAAAAAAUUAGCUGGGUGUGGUGGCGCAAACCUGUAGUCGUAGCUACUUGGGAGGCUGAGGCAGGGGAAUCACUUGAACCCCGGAGGCGGAGGUUGUAGUGGGCCGAGAUUGUGCCACUGCGCUCCAGCGUGGGCGACAGAGUGAGACUCCAUCUCAAAAAAAAAAAAAAAAAAAUCUAUGCUAGUAGAUUACAACUUCACACUAGAGGAGUUCUGGACAAAGCUUUUAAUUAGUCAAACUAAAUUAAGGCUCAUUAAAAGGAAAGGAACUACUGGGAAAUUAUGCAAUUCAAUAAUUUAGACUCUGUUACCAGGAUCUUUCAUAAAAAUUUAAUUUCCAUAAUCAUAACCUAAAUGAGUUCUUAAAGAAUUCUAUAAGCAAUAGCUGAUUAAUGGGCCCUGGAAGAUGAAGAUUAUAACUGUUUAUUUACCUAAUUAAAAGGAAAGGCAGUGCCAAAUAUGAGAGGAUAAACAAUAUUAGUUAACAUUUCUGUUAUUUAUGAUGCCAAUUAGUAGUAAGAUAAUUCCACAGCUGUCAACUUUGUUUGGGGCUGGCAACUUCUCUGCUUAAACAGGCUAAAAGUUUAGUAUUCUGGGAGAAGUGGCUGGAAGAAGGGGUAAUAUGGUGAAAGCAAAUUCCCUUUCCCAGGAGUCAAGAGAAUUUAUGUGAGGUGGCUCCCGCCUGUAAUCUCAGCACUUUGGGAGGCCAAGGCAGGCAAUCACCUGAGGGCAGGAGACCAGCCUGACUAACAUGGAGAAACCCCAUCUCUACUAAAAAUAC